CACAUGACAGUGUUUGUAUUGAGGACCUUCCAAGGAAGAGGGAUGCUGUAGCAGUGGUGCCUGGGUGCCUGGCCUCCAGUGUCCCACCUCCUUCACCACCCCACUUGGCUCCUUUGCCAUCUUGAUGCUGAGGUUUCCUGUUUGGUGAGAUCAGGUUGUUUGUGGUAAAAGAAAGGAAAGGGCUUCUGAUGGCUUUGCCACAAGCUUACCUGUGGGUUUCAGUCCUGAGAGGCCACCACCAGUUCCCAUCAGCACUGUCUCCAUGCAGCAGUUGCUGGGUCCCAUGUCCAGCUGCCUCUUUGGCUUCAUGGGUUUUUCUGCUUCCUGCCCCCACCCCCACAUGUGCAAUCCUCAAGAUUUGUCCUGAUUCUAUUUCCUGGCACCUCCCUGCCUGUCCUUGGGGAUUCUACUUCUUCCUGUGUGGGAGCCCAUAGCUGUUGUCUAACAGGUAAGAAAUGAAAUUGAACUAUUGACUGGGCCCCAGAAAUCCAUAAAAUGGCUGCAGACAGUUGUUUCUGUGUCCUGUUCUACCCCCACUCCAGUACAUAACUACUAUGUACUGUGUAGAGCCAUUCUAUAUGCUGAAUGUUCUGCUGUUGCAAACUUGCCAGGGUAUUAGCCAGUGUUUGUGCCAAGCAGUUUUCUGGGACAACAGAAUGACUCAGACCAAGAUGGAUAGGAUGGUUAGGGCUUUGCUUCUUGCUGUUUUUCUUUGAAGCUAGUUCAUUGUCCUGCAGGUCCCUUCAUCUUCCAUACCUAGCCCACUCUUUUAGCCCUUACCUUAAAUCUCUCAGAUAAGUUGGUUCACAAAGAAUGUUAAGUACUGAAUCAUGUGUGACUGAGACCAGAGAUGGCAAAUGAAUGGCACACCAUUUCUCCUUCUCCUGCCCCAGGGCAGGUACCACUGAUCUGCAUCAGAGUUGCCUGCUAUUCUCUGGUGUAUCCUUCACAUCUAGGUGCCCUCAAGCAGCUGUGUGAGUGUUGAGAUCUCUGCCAUCUCUGGCUGAGAUACUGCUGUCCUGUGAAGUGUUUCCCAUGACCUUUUUCUUCCCCUUUGAAUCCCUCUGUCUGGAGUAGUCCUUGCCUCUUCCUGCUCCAGUAGGGCCUUUUCCCUACCCCAGCCCCUGUGCCAGGCUAAGCUGGUACAAGAGCUGCCAACCUCACAGAGUGUUUGCUAGGCGAGAGAGGUGCAGGGAAGAGGCAGAGGUAUGCACCUUCCCCCUUGAAGAGAGGGGAAAGGCCUACAGUGGCCCACAUAAUUGCCUGACUCACACUUCAGCUACCUCUUAAUGCCUGUGGAGGGACUGGAGCUGCUGGAUCCCAGUGUGGUGGUGUAGGAGGCCACAGUGAGCAGGUGGCCCCAGCUGGGUUUCCCAGGUCAGGAAUGUGGGCCCCAGGCAAGGUGCAGCCUUUGCUCACAGCUCCAUCCAUGUCUAGACCUUCAGGCCAGUCUGCAGAUGAGGUUCCCUACCUUUUUCUUCUCUUCAUUGACCAAAUCAACCAAUCACUACAGCUGCUCUGCUUCUGCUUUCCAAAGUAGCCCAGGUCCUGGGCCAGAUGCAGGGGAGGUGCCUAUCCAUGAGUGAAGGCCAGUGUCUUCCUCACCUGGGUGGGUCCCACACUUGUGACCUCAGUUUUAGGACCAAGAUCUGUGUUGGUUUCUUAGAUUGCUAGCUUUUCCUCCAGGGGACCACAGCAGGUGAAGCUCAAGAGCGCAUGGCUCUGCUAAUAGUAAAUUGUUUUCAGGGCCUUGUCCAGCUGAGAGCUUCAUGUCCACCAGAUUCUGAGAGGUGUCAGCAGCACUUUUUUUUUUUAUUUGUUGUUUGUUUUCCAUGAGGUUAUCGGACCAUGGGCUGAGCUCAGGCACUUUCUGUAGGAGACUGUUAUUUCUGUAAAGAUGGUUAUUUAACCCUCCUCCACCCCAUCACGGUGGCCCUGAGGGCUGACCCGGAGGCCAGUGGAGCUGCCUGGUGUCCACGGGGGAGGGCCAAGGCCUGCUGAGCUGAUUCUCCAGCUGCUGCCCCAGCCUUUCCGCCUUGCACAGCACAGAGGUGGUCACCCCAGGGACAGCCAGGCACCUGCUCCUCUUGCCCUUCCUGGGGGAAGGGAGCUGCCUUCUGUCCCUGUAACUGCUUUCCUUAUGGCCCAGCCCGGCCACUCAGACUUGUUUGAAGCUGCACUGGCAGCUUUUUUGUCUCCUUUGGGUAUUCACAACAGCCAGGGACUUGAUUUUGAUGUAUUUUAAACCACAUUAAAUAAAGAGUCUGUUGCCUUACUUGUUUCUCUCCUGACCUGUGUAUUCCUUUGUUUCUGGAUCUGAUCCAUUCAGCCCCUUCCAUCAUCACUGACUUGUUCAGGUCUGCUGCAGAGCGCCCAUGGUGGUUCCCUGGUAUCUUACAUAUUCCACAGUGUCUUUGAGCAGUCGCCACAGCCUCAGGAUGCUGGCAUAUUCACUUGAGCUGCCUGAGUGGAGCCCUUGGCAAAGUUGGCAAGACCCUUGCCUCAGAGAGGAUCACACACACACAAAAAAGUUUUCCCUGACCUGGGGGCUCACAGGCUAGUGAAGGGAAAAGGUACUUUUAGCUAUAGACAGGUCAAUGGUGCUGAGAGCAGAGAGGAGGCCCCUGCCCCCUUCAGCAAGGUGAGGGGGUGAUACCUGGAAUGGCCUUCUGAACCACAGGGCAGGUAGAAGAUGAACGUCAUUUAGUGAUUAAAUGGUACAGCUGGGAAGCAGGUCCAUGGGACUGGGAGAGGGGGUGAGGCUGGGCCCAGAGUCUGGGUACCAGGUUAAGGAAUGUGGGCUAGAUCCAGAGGGCAGGGGGGGCAACUGAAGGUGUUUCAAUAGGAAAUUGAUAGGCUCCAGCAGUAAGGCAAAAGGCAUGGAGCCAGGCAUAGGCCAUUUGAGGCCCAGGUUAAGAGGGGUGGACACUCAUCACUGCUAUUUGGGUCUGAGCUGUGGGUAGGCUCCUAUAGCCCUGGCCUGCCCAAGGGAAUUCACAGGGGCCUCUAAUUGUAUGCAUUCCUUAAGGAGAGCACAUUCUCUGUUCAGUUUUUACACCCCCCAUUUACCCACCUCAAGCAUGGGACUCCUAUAUGGGAGACAUGCUGCUGGUGGCCUCACCCAGCACCCUGUUCUCUCUGGGUCCUGGGUUGGUCAGGCACAAAGGAUGAUAUGUGCUGAAUGCCCAGGAAAUGGCAGAGACAACCCACCUGCCCUUCCCUCCAGGCCUCCACAAAUAGAUGUGCCCACAAUGACUGUGACAGUCCCAGCAGAGCCUCUGACCCUUCUAGCUGGGUCCUGAUACAUGUUUUCCAUGCUGGCCAUGUUAUUUCUAGUCGCAGAUCCUCUGGAGGGUGUGGGGGGGGUGCCGCCCCAACUCUUGGAGAUUCCAAGCAAAGCAGCUCUGAGAAUAAUGAGGUUUCUGACCCCCCAGUGAAGCAGCUGAGGAUGGGAACCACAGGGGUGCUCCCUCUGUCAGCAGCAUUACCACUGUCUACUCUAGCAGCUCCGGUGGGGAAGGAGAGGGAUUUCUGUUGUCCCCAGUCUGGGCCCCUGGUUAUUGAAAAAGUUCGGAAUUACUCUUUACCCUUGUGGAGUGUUCUGAGUGUUGGAAGUACCCAGGAAGAAGCCCUGAGCAGGUGCCCUCAGGAGCAGUGCCCAUGGCUCCCCACAUCAGCCAAGAGGCCCAACCCCAGGAAGCCACUCCUGCCCGGGGAUGGGGAAGGUGGGCUGGGUGGCUGUGUGCACUGCCCUGGGCCAGCUCACUUGAGCCUGCUGAGCCGCCUGGCCAAACAUGAGCCUCUCUCCUGUUGUAUCAGAUGCUGUUCUGGGGACCUGCGCCAGGAGCCUCUGCCAGGGCUUUAAAUAGCUGCCCCCAUUGAUCUGGCUGCAGGCAGCAGCAGUCACACUGGGUCAGCCUCCAUCAGGUGCUCAGGUUUCCCUGAGGACUGGAGUCAGGUGCCAGGGAAUCGCGUGGUCUACCUUAUGACCUGGUGCUCCCCACACCUGUCUCCUAGGCCUGGGGGGUGGGGAGGACUCCUGUCACUUCAUCUGCGGCAAAAUACAGCCCCCACCACUUACCAGAGAAAACUGUCUGGCAUUGUAGAGAGAGGGGUUUUGCCCUCAAAAGACUGUUGCUUACUUUCAGUAGAAUGGGGAAUGACACUGGUAUCUUCCUUAAGGGUUGUUAUGGGGAUGAAAUGUAUGUAAAGUGCUCAAUAGGGCACUGGACUCACUCCAUUGAUGGCUGUCUUUGCUCGAAGUGUCUUCCUGAUGCUGCUGCUGUUGCUGCUUGUGCUUCUUCUGUGCUUACAUUCUCUCUCUCUCACUCACUCACUCUGUCUCUCCUCUCCCCCGCCCCACCCCCUUUCUGACAAAGCCACCACCAUUUUGUAAGGAACUGUAGCUUCUCUCUGAAACUGCCGGGAAAGGGAAAAUCUUUUUAAAAUAGACAUCACACAACCAACAGGGUCCCCUAGGUUCAGGCGGGGAGGUGAGGUCGAGUGAGAGGAACUGCUUAGCAUACGCGGGGAUGCUCCUCCCAUCUCACCCCACCGCGCUAAGGAGAAGGUCACUUUCUCUUUAAAUGCAAAUGAACUCCCUCCAGCUUAGCUUUCACCCGGUGGUGUUCCCGGGAGGAGAGGGCGGAGGGCGGAGGGAACUUGCACCGAAGCAUCACUCGAGACCCCAAACCUCCAGGUCAGUAGCCCCCUGAGGGAGUGAGGGCGGGGGCGGAAUGACGCGGGUCUGACGCUCUGUCUUCGAGCGCGGCUGCGGAGCUGAGCGAUGAGUUUGGCACAUGGCUUUGGAGCCCGGGCUUGGGAAAUAGAUCCCCGGUCGCCCCAGCCGCUCCUGGGGAGCACAGGCUCCGGCUCCAGUUCUUCUAUCAGGUCCCUAAUUGGGUCAAGCUGCUGCACGGAGAGGCAGAGGAUGCGCUCCUAUCUCCCCUCCCCACACCCGCAGACCCCGUCAGUGGCAGCCAGCUAUGUGUCAGUGUAAAUGCUUAAGCGCCACCCACCCCCCCAACCCCCCCAGUCCCAGAAUUCGAAGUUAGGCUCGGUAGCAGCAGCCUGGAAUGAGACCCCCAGAGGAGGGAACCCCAGCCGACCGGAGGCUUGGGGGGCGCUGCUGGACCGGGGACCUCGGAGCAGCCCAGCCACAGGCGCAGCCUUUGUCGGAGGCCCAGGCAGCCAGCGGCCAACCACCCAGUCCACCCUGGCUGCAGCUGAAGCCCAGCAGGGACUUUCCGACUGGGAAAAAUGAAGCAGCUGAAAGCACACCCGCGGGACCUAUAGGGAGUCCCUAAUAUUUUCGGUUGGGGGUGGGUGGAAGUGGAGGGAUGCCGGUGUCUAUGUGGGGGAAACCCACAAUGAACCCUGCCCUGUAUGCUGCGGCUUCUCCUACAAUUACCCACACGCUGGGGCUUUCCCAGGCGCCCCUACCUGCACCUUGUCCCCCUCCCAUGCUGACAGGGUUUGUUAGCAUCUGCUUAGGCCCCUGAUAAAUAGAAUAGGGUUUAGUUAAGACAUCCCUAAUCUUCGGCUGGGCUUCUGCAGCUCACCUCCGUCUUGUCUCCCACUACAUUUCCUCUGCCAGCCCCGCCCCCCAGCCACCGUGACAGGAAGCCCCAGUAGCGCCAAGAUAGUUGUGACUGGUCCCACCCUUUCAGGAGGGGCCUAGGUUUUCAGGCAGAAGGGGAAUUAGGUUGGGCCUUAGAAGGUCCUUCAAGUGUACAUCCACGAUCCCAGCAGCAGACACUGGCAUCUGGCUCUGCCCCUACCGUAUAGAUGAGGUGACAAGCUGGAAGGUCCCAGGGCCCUUCCUUGGUGCAGCUCUCAGGGAUUUCUGGGUGAAGGGCUAACUUUGCCCCUGGCUAUCUUUGUGGGGUUGCUUCCCUCCUAGGCCUGAGGCCCAGCCAGCGCCCAAUGGAUGACAAAAAGAAGAAACGGAGUCCCAAGCCCUGCCUGGCCCAGCCAGCCCAGGCCCCAGGCACACUACGGAGGGUCCCUGUGCCUACCAGCCACAGCGGCUCCUUGGCCCUAGGACUUCCUCAUCUGCCAUCCCCCAAGCAGCGGGCCAAGUUCAAGAGAGUAGGCAAAGAGAAGUGCCGCCCAGUCCUGGCUGGAGGUGGAAGCGGCUCUGCAGGCACGCCCCUGCAGCACUCCUUCCUGACCGAGGUGACUGAUGUCUAUGAGAUGGAGGGGGGACUCCUGAACCUGCUCAAUGAUUUCCACUCUGGCCGGCUGCAGGCCUUCGGGAAGGAAUGCUCCUUUGAGCAGCUGGAGCACGUUCGGGAGAUGCAGGAGAAGCUAGCCCGGCUGCACUUCAGCCUGGAUGUGUGUGGGGAGGAGGAGGACGAUGAAGAGGAAGAGGAUGGGGUCACUGAGGGGCUGCCAGAGGAGCAGAAGAAGACAAUGGCUGACCGUAACCUGGACCAGCUGCUUAGCAAUCUGGAAGACCUCAGUAAUUCUAUGUAUCCUUUCCAAGGAACCCGUCUAUGUGUGUGUGUUCCUGAGAGGUCAGUUUCCUCCUCUCCAGCCCUCCAGGAGUAUUCACACACAACCAACUUCCCCACCUCUUGCAGUCCUGUCAGAUUUAGCCACAGACUGCCCAAACCCAGGUACAGGAAUUUAGAAUUUCCCCAAAAUUAGAAGAAAAGUGGUUGUAGGGGAUGUUUUACUACUGAUCAAAAUCUUUGUGAGUACUUUAGCUGACAUCAAUCAUAGCAAAGCUUGUCCGAUGUCCUCCUAUCCUUUCAGCAUUGAACAAUUAUUUUUACUAAUUUACACUACCACCUCACCUGGUCCUCAGUCAGAAACAGCGCGAGUGCGCGCGCACACACCCCAGUGUGUCUGACCUGCACGAUCUGGAUGAAGAGAGAGGGGGUGAGAGAGGGCAGGCGGGGACUGCAACCUCAGUCCACAGACGGCCCGAGACCCUCGUCCCCGGCCCUUUGCACAGGUGAGGGAACUAAACCUGUGCAAGAUGGGAGACCGGGGUGGGAGGAAGGACUGGUCCAAAGCGCCACGAUCCUUGACGGGCACAGCCAGAAGCUGCACCUGGCCGAGAACGCCGAGCCUGAGGAGCAGUCCGCUGCGUAGGCGUCCCACGCAGGCCCACACUGCCCCUCUCAUUCUCUUCAAACUGUGACUUUUUACAGACUCGGGCGGGUGUUCUGCGGCCCCCCAGGUGCUAUGGGGGAGGGGGGCGUUGAAUGGAAUUAAACCAGAAAGAAAGCAA